GAGCAGGUCGCCGCUGGCUGGCAGUCGCCACCCGGUCCCAGAGUAAAUAAGGGAGAGACACUCCCGAGCGCCGUAAAUAGAGUCCAAGUGGGCGGAGAGCCGUCCCGCGCCGCCCGCUCAUGUCUCUACAGAGCCGACUGUCCGGCCGCCUGGCACAGCUGCGCGCGGCGGGGCAGCUGCUCGUCCCCCCGCGCCCCCGGCCCGGACACUUGGCGGGUGCCACGAGGACCCGCAGCAGCACGUGCGGUCCCCCGGCGUUCCUGGGCGUGUUCGGCCGCCGUGCGCGGACCUCGGCGGGAGUUGGGGCGUGGGGGGCGGCGGCGGUGGGGCGGACAGCCGGGGUGCGCACUUGGGCCCCCCUGGCCAUGGCGGCGAAGGUGGACCUGAGCACCUCCACCGACUGGAAGGAGGCGAAAUCCUUUCUGAAGGGCCUGAGUGACAAGCAGCGGGAGGAACAUUACUUCUGCAAGGACUUUGUCAGGCUGAAGAAGAUCCCGACAUGGAAGGAGAUGGCGAAAGGGGUGGCUGUGAAGGUGGAGGAGCCCAGGUAUAAAAAGGACAAGCAGCUCAAUGAGAAAAUCUCCCUGCUCCGCAGCGACAUCACCAAGCUGGAGGUGGACGCCAUCGUCAACGCCGGAGCCAAGAGGCUGCGCAUUAAUGAGACCCGUGCUGCCGCGGCCCUCCUGGAAUGUGAUCCGGAGCCUCAGGGAGGUUAAUUUAGUGAGAGCCAUGCAGCAGGCUUGGUUUCUUCUCUCAAGACUUCACACAAAGCCACUUUAUGGCCAACGCUAAAGGUACCAGUCAAUAUGGAUGGGAUGGAUUUAGGGCGUGUUUUAUGGAUUCAUAGCUGCUGUUUCCCUGGCACUGCACGAGGAGCACGCAUUGCUGUCUGGCUCGGACCCAGGAUUCGAAAGGAAAGCUUGUUGCUGGAAGGCCCAGGAGCUCAAAAGGGGGGCGUCGCCAGAACCUGCGGGAACGAAGCUGUCAGUGCCAUCACUGGCGAGGAGUGGAGAGCAGGGAGCUUCAUUGUCUGGUGUUAAAACAACAUGUCCUGUUGUCACUCGUACAUUCUACAGACAGAAGAAUGAGGUGUCAACAGAAUCACUUUCUCAUGUAUUUACAGAAAUCUCUUUUCAUCAGAGGUGCCUCCCUGGCCCUGGGUUCCGAGUUGUGUGGGAAAUUGUCCCACACCUUGCCCCUUUCUCAAAUCAUAAACUUUCAGCUAUUCAAAAAAAAAAAAAGUGGUCUGUUUUCUUGCACUUAAAGGAAUGAGACAAAUAAAAGGAGGGAGGAGUCACGUCUGUACUCUGAGGGAAUUGGCUGCAAGGUGUAAUUUUGGAUUUCACAAAUGGAAAAAUAGCAGCAUAGAUUUUUCUUAUAUUAUUUUACUGUUCAUAGUGGUAAAAAAUCAAUUAAAGAGAAAUUAUCUUUCA